AAUGUUGGCCAGGUUGGUCUCAAACUCCUAACUGAAAGUAAUCCAUCAACCUUGGCCUCGCCAAGUGCUGAGAUUAUAGGCGUGAACCACUGUGCCUGGCCCACCUACUUCCAGUUUAAAGUCACCUGGGAAAUACUUGGAGUACAGUUUUGUCAUUUUAAUCCUUUUUUGGACCACAACAAUCACUUUACGAACAUUUUUUUAACUUUUUCAGAAUCGAUUCAAGGAAAAGUGAUAGAGGCAGGUGGGGACGGGGAGGUGAGUUUUCUUCGCAUUUUUGGGAAUCUCAACUCCUGAGCCUGUCUUACUAGUACGGGUUCCCCAACCCCACGACUAGAACUAUCUUAGUGGUUUCUUCCUAAAGAGAUGUACACGUGUGUGUGUGUGUGUGUGUGGUGGGCGUGGGUGGGUGUGUAGAGUAGGGAAAAGGUGAGAAGUGGCUCUCUUGCUAUAGACUUUUGCUUUUUACUCUUUUCCACUGAGUCUGCUCAUAUUAUUCAUACGAUUAUCACGUUAGAGGUUUUGGAGUUGUAGUGGCUAUCGUUUUAAGUUUCUUGUAGAAUUAAUUUAUAUAAGUAGACAAUGUAUAUGAAUUGAUUGAUUCAAAUCUGUAUCUUACAGGAUCUGUUAAAGAUAGUCAGAAGGCUGUCUUUUAAAAUGUGAGGACAAAUCAGUUUAACAGUAUAGCAGAGAAGUACAGCUGUGCUCUGUCAAACUCUAGGCUCCUGUGUGUUGGAAUGACUAGAGGCAGCAGGGAGAGGGGUCCUGGUUUACUCACCCCCUCUCCCUCUUUCACAUACUAGCUUGGGCUUGUUGUGGUUGAGGUGGUGUGGGAACAUCUAGAAGGUUCAUUCAAAAAAGACAGCCUCAGCCUUUGCUCAGACGCUCAAGAUGUUCUGCCGGCUCUCCCUACCAUGAAAGUUCUCUGAGAAGCCAGUAAAGAUGGCAGCCUCUAAAGAGGUUAGCUUUAUUUGGUGGAGGGGCGGUAGGGGUGGCACACACCGAGGAAGAUUCGGAUCGUGGCACAUCCUUGUGGUCAGGCCCAGAAAUCCUCAUUGCCCUGCAGCCACCCAGGUCAUGAUUCAUGAGGUGGGGGUCUAAGCUGAGAAUGGCUGGCCGGUUCUCUGACUUCGUGGGUGUGUAAUAGUUGGUUGCAACUGACUUCUCAAGAAUGACAGUUACUGACUGGAGCUGGCAGAGAGGUGUGGCCAAGUUCCUGGAGAAAUGCUUCCUGCUCCUCCCGCCCUCCCCACCACCAUCCUGCUGUAUUUAAAGCUGCUUUGGUGAUGCUUUGCUCAUCUCAGUGAAUUUUCAGUUCAGACCUUUUCACUAAGGAUCAUUAUGGAAGAAAGAGGGGUAAGAAGUGUGGCUGAGUAGCCUAGGAUUAAUUCAUCAGUCCCCAAAUAAGCAAACACGAUGUCUCAGGAUGGACGGUGAAAUUCUGGACCUCACAGGACCCUGCUUUCUCGGCUGUGAUUCACGACAAACUCCAGGUCCCCAACACCAUCCGGAAGGCAUGGAACGACCGGGACAACCGCUGUGACAUUUGCGCCACUCACCUGAACCAGUUGAAGCAGGAGGCCAUCCAGAUGGUGCUGACGUUGGAGCAGGCAGCCGGCAGUGAGCACUACGACGCCUCGCCCUGCUCCCCGCCACCGCUCUCCAACAUCCCCACCCUGGUGGGGUCCCGGCACGUGGGUGGGCUCCAGCAGCCCAGAGACUGGGCCUUUGUGCCCGCCCCCUGUGCCACCUCCAACUACACAGGCUUCGCCAACAAGCACGGCAGCAAACCCAGCAGCCUUGGGGUCAGCAAUGGGGCGGAAAAGAAGAGCGGGUCCCCAACCCACCAGGCCAAGGUCAGCCUCCAGAUGGCCACCAGUCCAAGCAAUGGGAACAUCCUCAAUUCGGUGGCCAUCCAGGCUCACCAGUACCUGGAUGGCACCUGGUCCCUGUCGAGAACCAACGGGGUCACCCUGUACCCAUACCAGAUCUCCCAGCUGAUGACAGAGAGUAGCCGGGAGGGACUAACAGAAGCAGUGCUGAACCGCUACAAUGCAGACAAGCCUUCCGCCUGCAGUGUCCCAGCCUCGCAGGGCUCCUGCGUGGCCAGCGAGACUUCCACAGGCACAUCGGUGGCCGCCUCCUUCUUUGCACGAGCUGCCCAGAAGUUAAAUCUGUCUUCUAAAAAGAAGAAACAUCGGCCUUCCACUUCUUCCGCUGCCGAACCACCGCUCUUUGCAACCAGCUUCAGUGGGAUUCUGCAGACCUCCCCUCCCCCAGCCCCACCCUGCCUGCUGAGGGCUGUCAACAAGGUGAAGGACACCCCGGGGCUGGGCAAGGUGAAAGUCAUGCUUCGCAUCUGUUCCACCUUGGCUCGAGAUACUUCAGAAUCCAGCUCUUUCUUAAAGGUGGACCCACGGAAGAAGCAGAUCACCUUGUACGAUCCCCUGACUUGUGGAGGUCAAAAUGCCUUCCAAAAGAGAGGCAACCAGGUUCCUCCAAAGAUGUUUGCCUUCGAUGCAGUUUUUCCACAAGACGCUUCUCAGGCUGAAGUGUGUGCAGGCACCGUGGCAGAGGUGAUCCAGUCUGUGGUCAACGGGGCAGAUGGCUGCGUGUUCUGUUUCGGCCACGCCAAACUGGGAAAAUCCUACACCAUGAUCGGAAAGGAUGAUUCCAUGCAGAACCUGGGCAUCAUUCCCUGUGCCAUCUCUUGGCUCUUCAAGCUCAUAAACGAACGCAAGGAAAAGACCGGCGCCCGUUUCUCAGUCCGGGUUUCCGCCGUGGAAGUGUGGGGGAAGGAGGAGAACCUGCGGGACCUGCUGUCGGAGGUGGCCACGGGCAGCCUGCAGGACGGCCAGUCCCCGGGCGUGUACCUCUGUGAGGACCCCAUCUGCGGCACGCAGCUGCAGAACCAGAGCGAGCUGCGGGCCCCCACCGCAGAGAAGGCUGCCUUUUUCCUGGAUGCCGCCAUUGCCUCCCGCAGGAGCCACCAACAGGACUGUGAUGAGGACGACCACCGCAACUCACACGUGUUCUUCACACUGCACAUCUACCAGUACCGGAUGGAGAAGAGCGGGAAAGGGGGAAUGUCUGGAGGUCGCAGCCGCCUGCAUCUCAUUGAUCUCGGCAGCUGUGUGAAAGCUCUUAGCAAAAAUCGAGAAGGAGGCUCAGGGCUGUGUCUCUCGCUGUCUGCUCUGGGCAAUGUCAUCCUGGCUCUCGUCAAUGGCAGCAAACACAUUCCAUACAAAGAGAGCAAGCUCGCCAUGUUGCUGCGGGAGUCUCUGGGGAACAUGAACUGCCGUACCACCAUGAUCGCGCACAUCUCGGCCGCGGUCGGGAGCUACGCGGAGACCCUGUCCACCAUCCAGAUUGCAUCGAGAGUCUUGAGGAUGAAGAAAAAGAAGACGAAGUACACAUCCAGCUCGUCCGGCGGGGAGAGCUCCUGCGAAGAAGGCCGCAUGCGCAGGCCCACCCAGCUGAGACCCUUCCACACCAGGGCCACGGUGGACCCUGACUUCCCCAUCGCUCACCUGUCCAGCGACCCCGACUACUCCUCCAGCAGCGAGCAGUCCUGCGACACCGUCAUCUACAUCGGGCCCAACGGCACGGCCCUCUCUGACAAGGAGCUCACCGACAACGAGGGCCCCCCAGACUUUGUCCCUAUCGUGCCAGCCCUGCAGAAGACCCGGGGCGACAGCCGGCCCGCAGAGGCAGGAGAGGCUGCAGCCGGCAAGUCAGAAAGGGACUGCCUGAAGUGCAACACGUUUGCCGAGCUGCAGGAGAGGCUGGACUGCAUCGACGGCAGCGAGGAGCCCAGCAGCUUUCCUUUCGAAGAACUGCCUGCUCAGUUUGGGCCAGAGCAGGCAAGCAGAGGCCCCCGGUUAAGCCAAGCAGCGGGGGCAAGCCCACUCUCUGAGUCUGAUAAGGAAGAUAAUGGGUCCGAAGGUCAGCUGACCAACAGAGAAGGCCCUGAACUCCCAGCCUCCAAGAUGCAGAGGAGUCACUCACCUGUGCCCGCCGCGGCACCCGCCCACAGCCCCAGCCCGGCCUCACCCAGGAGCGUCCCGGGCAGCAGUAGCCAGCACAGCGCCUCCCCACUCGUGCAGAGCCCCAGCCUCCAGAGCAGCCGGGAGAGCCUCAACUCCUGCGGCUUCGUGGAAGGCAAGCCCAGGCCCAUGGGCUCCCCCCGGCUGGGCAUCGCCAGCCUGUCCAAGACCUCGGAGUACAAGCCACCCAGCUCUCCUUCCCAGAGAUGCAAAGUCUACACCCAGAAGGGGGUCCUGCCGUCUCCCGCCCCACUGCCUCCCUCGAGCAAGGAUUCCGGCGUGGCGUCUAGGGAGUCCUUGCUGCAGCCCGAGGUGCGUACGCCCCCGGUUGGAAUGAGCCCCCAGGUUUUGAAAAAAUCCAUGUCUGCUGGGAGCGAAGGGUUCCCGGAAACUCCUGUCGAUGAUGAGCAGCAGGCAGCUACUCCUUCAGAGUCCAAGAAGGAGAUCCUGAGCACCACGAUGGUGACGGUGCAGCAGCCACUGGAGCUGAACGGUGAGGACGAGCUGGUGUUCACGCUGGUGGAGGAGCUGACCAUCAGCGGGGUCCUGGACAGCGGCCGCCCCACCAGCAUCAUCAGCUUCAACAGCGACUGCUCUGCACGGGCCCUGGCCUCGGGCUCGCGGCCCGUCAGCAUCAUCAGCAGCAUCAGCGAGGACCUGGAGUGCUACUCCAGCACGGCCCCCGUCUCCGAGGUCAGCAUCACACAGUUCUUGCCCCUCCCGAAGAUGAGCCUGGAUGAGAAGGCCCAGGACGCAGGGAGCAGACGCUCUUCCAUCAGCUCCUGGCUGAGCGAGAUGAGCGCGGGCAGUGAGGGUGAGCAGUCGUGCCACAGUUUCAUAGCCCAGACGUGUUUUGGGCACGGGGAGGCAAUGGCAGAACCUGUGGCCUCGGAGUUUGUCAGCAGCCUCCAGAACACCGCUGUGGUGUGCAGAGAGAAGCCCAAGGCCAGCCCCGACAACUUGCUCAUCCUGUCUGAGAUGGGAGAUGACUCUUUCAACAAAGCAGCCCCCAUCAAAGGCUGCAAAAUAUCCACAGUGAGCAAGGCCAUGGUCACCAUCUCCAACACGGCCAAUCUGAGCAGCUGCGAGGGGUACAUCCCCAUGAAGACCAAUAUCACAGUUUACCCCUGCAUUGCCAUGAGCCCCCGGAACAUCCAAGAGCCGGAGGCCCCCACCGCCACCCCCAAAGCAGGCCCCACAUUAGCCCAGUCCCGGGAGAGUAAGGAAAACAGUGCAAAGAAAGAGAUGAAAUUUGAGGACCCGUGGCUGAAACGAGAAGAGGAAGUGAAAAAAGAGACGGCUCAUCCCAAUGAAGAAGGGAUGAUGAGGUGUGAGACUGCCACGGGCCCCUCGAAUGCUGAGACCAGAGCAGAGCAGGAGCAGGACGGAAAGCCCAGUCCGGGAGACAGGCUCAGCAGCAGCAGCGGAGAGGUGUCGGCCUCCCCGGUCACUGACAACUUCAGGAGGGUCGUGGAUGGGUGUGAGAUGGCCCUGCCCGGUUUGGCCACCCAGAGCCCCGUGCAUCCCAACAAAAGCGUCAAGUCCAGCAGCCUUCCCAGGGCCUUUCAGAAGGCCAGCCGGCAGGAGGAGCCGGACAGCCUCUCCUAUUACUGCGCUGCUGAGACCAACGGGGUGGGUGCAGCCUCGGGCACCCCGCCCUCCAAGGCUACCCUGGAGGGGAAGGUGGCUUCCCCCAAGCACUGUGUUCUGGCUCGGCCCAAAGGGACUCCCCCUCUGCCCCCUGUCCGAAAGUCCAGCCUGGACCAGAAGAACCGGGCCAGCCCUCAGCACAGUGCCAGCGGCAGCGGCACCAGCAGCCCCCUGAACCAACCAGCCGCCUUCCCGGCGGGCCUCCCAGACGAGCCUAGCGGCAAGACGAAGGACGCCAGCAGCAGCAGCAAGCUCUUCAGUGCCAAGCUGGAGCAGCUGGCCAGCAGAAGCAACUCGCUGGGCAGGGCGACAGUCAGCCACUACGAAUGCCUCUCCCUGGAGCGGGCCGAGAGCCUGUCCUCCGUGAGCUCCCGGCUGCACGCGGGCAAGGACGGCACCAUGCCCCGCGCGGGGAGGAGCCUGGGCCGCAGCGCCGGGACCUCGCCCCCCAGCUCCGGGGCCUCGCCCAAGGCCGGCCAGUCCAAGAUCUCCGCCGUGAGCAGACUCCUCCUGGCCAGCCCCAGAGCGCGCGGCCCGUCCGCCUCCACCACCAAAACCCUCAGCUUCUCCACCAAGUCCCUGCCGCAGGCGGUGGGCCAGGGCUCCAGCUCGCCCCCCGGUGGGAAGCACACGCCCUGGUCCACGCAGUCCCUCAGCAGGAACAGGAGCUCGGGCCUGGCCUCCAAGCUUCCCCUGCGGGCCGUCAGCGGGCGCAUCUCGGAGCUGCUGCAGGGUGGCGCGGGCGCCCGGGGCUUGCAGCUGCGGGCCGGGCCCGAGGCGGAGGCGCGCGGGGGGGCCCUGGCCGAGGACGAGCCCGCGGCCGCGCACCUGCUCCCGUCGCCCUACAGCAAGAUCACGCCCCCGCGGAGGCCCCACCGCUGCAGCAGCGGCCACGGCAGCGACAACAGCAGCGUGCUGAGCGGGGAGCUCCCGCCGGCCAUGGGGAAGACGGCCCUGUUCUACCACAGCGGCGGCAGCAGCGGCUACGAGAGCGUGAUGCGGGACAGCGAGGCCACCGGCAGCGCGUCCUCGGCGCAGGACUCCACGAGCGAGAACAGCAGCUCCGUGGGCGGCAGGUGCCGGAGCCUCAAGACCCCGAAGAAACGCUCCAAUCCAGGUUCUCAGAGACGGAGGCUUAUCCCAGCACUAUCCCUGGACACCUCUUCCCCUGUGAGAAAACCCCCCAACAGCACAGGCGUCCGCUGGGUGGAUGGCCCCUUGCGGAGCAGCCCGAGGGGCCUUGGGGAACCCUUUGAGAUUAAAGUCUAUGAAAUCGAUGACGUGGAGCGCCUGCAGCGGCGACGAGGGGGUGCCAGCAAGGAGGCCAUGUGCUUCAAUGCAAAGCUGAAGAUUCUGGAACACCGCCAGCAGAGGAUCGCCGAGGUCCGCGCGAAGUACGAGUGGCUGAUGAAGGAGCUGGAGGCGACCAAACAGUAUCUGAUGCUGGAUCCCAACAAGUGGCUCAGUGAAUUUGACUUGGAGCAGGUUUGGGAGCUGGAUUCCCUGGAGUACCUGGAGGCACUGGAGUGUGUGACGGAGCGCCUGGAGAGCCGUGUCAACUUCUGCAAGGCCCAUCUCAUGAUGAUCACCUGCUUCGACAUCACCUCCAGGCGCCGGUAGAUGAGCCAGACCCUUGUCCUAGUGGUCCCCCGCUCCCCAGGACUUCAGAGAUGUUGCACGCCCCUAGGCCCUCUGUGCUGGGGCAUCAAAGACAAUGAAUGAGGAUGAAGGUUGGUGGCAAGUCUGGAGCGGGCGUUGAGCGGAAGGCGAGUUUUCUUUUGUUUUCUGUAGGAAAGGUGCAAACGUCAAACACCGUGGAAGGAGAAAAGGAUGGGAAGCCCGAGGGGUGUCCAAGCCCUGUGAGACUGAAAAAGCACUUUGAGGAACCUUAAAGACCUUGUUUGUACAUAAGAACUGCUAGCAAAAGAGACCUCACUCUUCUCUUGCUUUCGUGAGAAAGGAGGGGCGUGGAUGUAGGAUUGCUGUGGAAAGCGAACACAAAACAACCCAGAAUGACUGAUUAAGUGCCUUGCAAAUCUUUAUUAUUAUCCAAACAUUUAUGUUCAUACUUUCUUGUGUACAGAUGGUGCUAGUCAAGAUGAAAACAACAAAACAAACAAGAAAAACAUUUUGGAAAUGUAUUCACAGCUCUUUUUCUCUUGGUGUUUUAUCCUAUUUCUGACUUGCUGUUUCUAAGUAAGUUGUGUUUGUAGAGCUAUUUCUUAAUCAGUAUUGCUUAUGAAUAAAUAUUACCUGUCUUUUAUGGUUAUUCUGGUGAGGCCACUCAAACAGAGAGACUUCCCUCGGCACGAGCCAGUGUGUGUGUUUCCAAAGUAGGUUUGGAGCAGCAGGUGACCUCGAUGCCACAUCCCAACAAGCAGCGUGGUCAGGUAGACCCAGAAGGUUGAUUGUGGGGCAGGUGCUUUAGAGAACAGGUGAGGAGACGGCACCUGCAGCACAGGGGAGGAGGAGUCCUUUGCGACCUGGGCCCUCCCUGCUCCUGGGAGGUGGGCCGUAUGUUCUGUAGACCGUUUGCCCCCCUCAAGUCCUCCACACAUGUGGUUCCUUGACCCACAAAUCCACAGUUUGCGUGGCCCUCAAAAUUCAUAUUCAUUUUUAUUCCAAAAAGUCUUGAACGAAAGCUGGAACCAAUUCACCAGAGCCAUAUUUCUUUCUUUAGUAUUUUCUAGUGUUGUGUUGUAGAUUGAUUAAAGUGGGUUUUUCCCCAGCUGAGAGACCUUCUCAGGCUUGUUCAGAGACUUCAACUGUAUUGGAUUAGAAGAAGGAUUCUUGAGACUGUACAUCUUGUCUGUUGUCCAGAGUACAAGGAUUUCAGCUCUCCUGUGUCCCAAAGCCUCUAUGCCAAGAAGGGACAGGCUUGUCCUCUCAGUCUUUGCUCCUGCCCAAAGGCAGAGAGAGCUUCCCCUCCAUAACUCACACGACCCUGGAUAGGCAGAACAUAGCUGAAGACUAUGGAUGUCCAGGUCUUGGCUCCCAACAACUCAGGACCUCAAAUUCAGAUGUUCCUCCCUAUAACAAUUCCCUUAGGAAUUAUGAUACCCAUUUUAGUGAUUGAUAGAAACCUGGGGUACAGAGUGGUCAAGGGAUUUCCCUGAUAAAAGCUGUGGUGCUGAUGAUAGUGCAGCCCAGAAUCUAAGAGUCCCUGCAGCCUUCGCAUCGAGGAUGGUACUUAGGCGUGUGCAGAGCACGCUUCCCUUUUGCCCUCAAAUGCAGCAUAUCUUCAUGAGCCUAUUUAUUUCCAAGCUAGGCUGUCUUUAUUAACCAACAACUCAGCCCCAGCCACUCCCCAAGCGGGGAAAAAAACACUACGUUUCUUGGUCAGUGUACCUCUGGACACUGCAGCCCACACAGCUGGCUGAACUCGGUAAAUGGGAACCGAAGUCUUGUGAGCUUCACAUGACCUGAUCCUUUGUUAUCAGAACAGGGUUCAGGUGGCCCUGUUGGCUCAUGUGCUUUGGAAGCCAGCUCCCUGGGUCACGAGUCUGGCUUUGCACUUUCCAUAAGAGUCUGCUUCUAUGCAAAGGUGCAAACAGGAGACAUGCCCAAAUCUGCUGGCUGAACAGGCUAAACUACAGUGAGAGGCUGCUCUGGCAUGGCUCGUUCUUCCUUCUGUGUAUCUCCCAAGUCUGACAAGUGUGUUGCCCUGGGAAGCAGGACCUCCCUGAGCUCCUUAACCUUGACCCCAUUCUGCAGGACAGUCGCAUGCUCUGGGCUCGCCUCUGGCCUCAAAGCACUUGUGUAAGUGGGCUUGCUUAACAGUAAUAUCCUUGGAGGCUUCUGGACCCAAAGGGAAGCCAAUCCUUCGAGUUUGCCAUUGGGCUGCUGGUUGCUGGUUUCAAACAUAUAGUUCAUGAAAAGUCUUUAAUUGGAGAUUUUCAAAGGUGAAUAUUCUGUUUUUGUUGGAAAGAAACUCAUCUGAUGAGUCAUCGAUGAGUUUGGCUUUCGCCCCUGCCACAUCCUCCCCUGAGGUUCCUUCCAUGCUGCACUGCCUUCCUUUAGCCAGUGACAGAGCCUGGUGCCCUUCCUGGACUGAAACCGAUGGAAUCCUUCCGAGGGGAGUGGCAUUCGGCUUGCCUCCUGCCUAAAUCUGCUUUUAUCCAUUUGUAGCAACUUUAUGCUGUAACAAAAGGCGGAAGGAAACCAAGAGUUCUCUUAGCAAGUCAGACUCCUUCCCAAGAUGGCAAUCACAGAACACCUCGCAGGAUCUCGCAGGCCACGGUGAAGGAGAAUGCUUUAUGUUGAUGUUGUCCAUUCUCUCUCUCUUCUCUUUGCUUUUUUUUGACCUAAAUAAGCUGCAAACAUGUUAAUUUACCAAUAUUGAUAAACCACAUGAAGAAAUCAGGCAUUUUACGUUAUGAUGUGCUUGUUCCUGUCUCUGCCUAUAAAUUGACUGUAUUGAUGAUGAAGGAAGGAGUUCCGGCUGACCAUUCUGAAGCAGUCCCAGUCACGGGAGGAUGCCUUACCCAGUGGCCAGACAUGAUAGUUCCAGGUCUCCCCUUGGUUUUGGUGAUAGAGAACCCAAGGAGGCAAGGGGGAAUAUCAACGAACCCAUUUCUAUUUCAUUACCCACAAGCGAAAGGACUAGAAAAAAAUAUUUGAAAUUAACAUUUAGAUGCAUAGGUCUAACUCCUUGUGUGAACCUGUCCUCCUCACCCCCUGCUCCAAAUAUGUGAGGUGGAAGCAUUAGCAGCGGAGCAAAACUAAGAUCUAAGAACGGGCGGUGGUGCUAUUGUGUCCCUGGGAGUCACUCCACGUCGCAUUGCACGGUGGUGCUGAGGAGCGAGAGUUUGCUUUAUCAUGGGCUUUCAGUUCCCACCUGCGAGCUGCAAACUUUGAUCUUGUUGUCCUUGAAUUCCCCUCUACAUCACGAGGAAGCUGUCUCUUUCAUCUCUUCCGGAUUUGGAAUCAGAACACUCUGCCCGUUGUUUAUUCGCCAGUUGCCAUUCUUAACAUGGGGGAGCAUUAAGAUGCAAAUGCAGAGAUGUGUCCUGUCUUGACAAAGGUGGGAACCCCUGAGCUGGAGAAGGGGCUCCUCUCAUGAGAAGCUGGGGUAAACAGCCAGGCAUCGCAGCGUGGGGAAUUAGACAGGCAGGAAUCUGGCCUGGUUUGUCAUAAAUUAGCCUUCAACUUGAAGUCUAUUAUGUUCUUAUAAGGCGGUAGUGACUUCAGUCCAGCCGCAUCUACCAUCCAGGGUGGAGGUUCAAAAAGUCUUAUACGCACCUACAAGUCUCACGCUUGCUGCUCAGACUUUCUGAUAAAAUCUCAGAGUUCUGUUUGUAUUGACCAAAAAUGCAGUUGUGCCCACUUGGGUGUGUAUCUCAUGUCCUUGUAAACCAGCCACCUUCUUUGGAUAGAAGGCAAGGCUGACAAAUCUGCAGAUUUGUUCAAUGCAAACACAGCCGUCUAUAUCAUUGGCCACUGCUGAUUAUAUUGAGUGUUUUUAGGUUUUUUAGGUUUCUUAUUCCAAAAAGGAUUUUAGACUGUAAAAUGACUAAAGAUGAGUUAAUUUCCAAACUAAAAAAGGAAGGAGUCCUGCCUGUACUCAUUGUUCUUUCCUGCUGGACUAGUAACCCAUUCUUGGAGCACACACAGAGUCCCUCGCUUCUAAAGACAAUACGUCUUAAACCCUGAAAACUUGCCAGUGAGAAAGAGGUUGAAAGUCCUGUUUGCUAUUAGUUGAGGCUAAGCCGUCUGCUGCCACUGUCCCUGGGGCCUCCAUGCUGCCGCCGGGGUAUGUGGCCCAGCUGUCCCCCCAUGAAGGACACUCUUCAAUGCCACCACACGGGAGUCUGGGCAGGGAGGAAAGGCACACAGCCCACUUUUCUCUGCACCAAAUGAAACAAAGCUGGGUGUUCAGUGUCACUGAUGCAAGUAAAUGGGUCUCAAAUUUUGGUGGGGGCAGUGUUUCUUUGGAUUCUGAUACCUCUUUUUCCACCUCCAGAAAGUAUCUGUCAACAUUGGUGGGUAACAGCUUAUAAAGUGCAUCACUUAGUAAUCUUCCUGACAAAAUGACACAUUUUAAAAUUACAACCUGUUCAUUAUUUCCAUCAUAAUGCAAGCGUAAUUCUAAUCCGGGAGAAGAUACUGUCAUUUAAGCUCAUCUUCUCAAAAAAAUUUUUUCUGAAAAUUCCUGGAAACUAAUUUAUCCCUCCCUAAACAAACACAUUCUGCUUUUGGGUGGCCCUACCCAGAACCUGCAGCAAUGUCAUAACACUGGACACAGUGCGGCUUGGGGCAGUAUCAAGCCUUCAUUGCAUACAAACCUUAAUCUCUAAGCAUAGUUGUUCCCAAGGUCCACACGUGUGGAGGCGAGUACUGAAAUACCACACUCACACAUCUAUUCCAUGCGUACCUAGAAAUUACCUUCAACACUAAAAAAGGUUCCUUCUUUCAUUCCCUAUCCUGCUAACAGCCCACAUUGUAAUAUUUGAUUUAUGAAGAAGUUCUAAUUUAUUUGUGAACUCAGGAUGUUGCUUUACAGCAUUGCUCGUGUUCUCUCAUUUACUUAUUAUGCAUCACGGUUGGAAAUGCUAUCCACGUGCCGUGCAUCGAGGUGGAGAUUUGCUGGAUCUGUCUGUGGCUAUUUUUUUCCAUGUUUUUCUCACUCAAGCAAAGUCUGUUAGUGGAAACAUGGGCUGGGGGAUGGGGAGAGGACAGAUAAAGCAAGAGAAUAGGGAUUAGGGUCCAAUCCUCAAUGCACAGGGCUUAGUUCAAAAUCUAAGCUGUUUCUGUAGUAAGCAGCCAAAUGGGAAAGAUCCCUUCGUUUUGAAUUUGAUGAGAAUGGGCUUGGAAAUCCACGCCCACCGGCUUGCACGGAAGAGGACUCAGCCUCUUCCUAAUGGUUCAACAUUCAAUUCCUGAGGAAAGUGCUGAUAGUAUUAGUUCCCUACAUUUCCCUAAGACUCCCAUCCAACCCCUAGUGCUACUGAAGAGGGUUUGGGAAAGCAAUUGGAGUUCCUUAGCUUGGAUAUAUAUAGUACCUGUUUUUUUCCUCUGGAAAAACCAAAGUACUUUAGUGAGUCUUACAAUCUUAAGGCAUUUUGUCCCCUCACUGGGUCCCGAGAGGCAGGGAGGGGCUAGGCCUUGAGCUAGGAGCAAGGACAUGGGCCGCCAGGCCUGGUUGUUACUAGCUGUGCAACCUUGGGCGAGCCUCUUCGCUUUGCUGGGCCUCAGGUUCCCGAGUGGAAGACUGGGGGUCAGAACAGCUGCCCUUCUGGGAGAGCAUCAAGAGAAAGUGGUAUAAGUGAUGGGAAGUGCUUUGAAGAAAUUAAAGGUCUGUCUAGGAGCUGGGGGUAAUCAUUUACAGAUGAAGAAACUGAAGUCUAGUCAUUGACUGGCCCGAGUUCACAGAGUGGUUUUAUAGCAAAACAGGGACUUGAGUCCAGCUUAUUGGAUUCUUCCCAUCAGAUCAUAUUGCACCAGGUAUGUGUAGACAUGAACACAUACCAUUCCUCUAAGGUGUGUGUACAUACACGGAUGUGUGUGUACAGGAGGUACCUGACAUGGUGAAAGGCCAUAGGACAGAAAACCUGAGUUCUAAUUCCAGCUUUGCCAGUCGUCCCGUCCGUGAUAUAUUCCAUAGGACAGAAAACCUGAGUUCUAAUUCCAGCUUUGCCAGUCAUCCUGUCCGUGAUAUAUUCCAUAGGACAGAAAACCUGAGUUCUAAUUCCAGCUUUGCCAGUCGUCCCGUCCGUGAUAUAUUACCUAACUCCUCCAGAACUCAGUUUUCUAACCUAUAAAAUGAAGACAUUGUGCUAGAUGAUCUUUGUGGUUCCUUCAAGCUCUGGAUCUCUAAUUCCAUGAUUAGUAAUGUAUGUAUGUGUAUAUAAAUAUGCUUAUCUGUAGAAAUGGGCCCAUUUGAAAAGUGGAGACAAGGUCUGCCCAGGUGCAUUUAUUGUGCCAGAAACAGUGAAUUCCUAAAUAAGUUCAUAAAAUCUUGUUUUACAAUUCAAUGGUAGUGCUUAAUGUUACUGUCUGAAAUCCACUGUUUAACCAGAUGGAAGACUGGGGCCAUUCAAAACAUUAUUAGUUCACAAGUGUUUGCUGUUAAAAUGCUUCAAUAAAACUCAUUUGUUAAAGUCAGAAAUUCAACUCUUCUGUACUUGGGCAGGUCCCAGCAGCCCCUUGGCAGGCUAGUUUUGUGCAUGGGCCUUUGCAAGCUAUAUAAACGUUAGGUGUUGGCUUGAUUAUGAUAAAUAUGAGCAGGCUCCCUGGAGAACAGUCCAGAAAAAAAGAGUUAUAGUUCUCACAAACUGGUGACAUGAAUCCAUUAAGCUGUGUGGCAUUUUCCAGUGUAAAGACAUUGUUUGCUGGCUACGAUCUCUGACUUUUUGUGGCAUAUGAGGUGUAAAAUGUUGUCAAAAAAGAAUCUGGUGUUUAAAAAAAAAUCAAACUAUGGUGGCAUUAAAUGUUCACUUUUAUUCUA